AUGUGUGUACUGUGUGUGUGGUCCUUGAUAGAUUAUGGAAUUUUUUAAAAACCAUAAACACCUUGUUUUUGACAAUUGGGGAAACUUAUAUGUAGAUAAUUAUCAAUGUUAACUUUCUUGGAUGUGAUAAUGAUAUUGUAGUUACAUAGGAGAUUGUCCCUGUUUGUAGGAGAUGCAUGCUGAAAAGGUUUUGGGGGAGUGAAAGGUAUACAGUUUAAGUCGUUCAGGUGGAAAAAGUGUAUGUAGAUGGAAAUAAAGCAAAUACAGCAAAAUGUUACUGAUCAUUGAUAUAGAUGAAGAGUGGUGUUUAUUGUACCAAACUUUCAACUUUUCUUUAGGUUAAAAAAUUUAAAAAUAAAAAGGGAUAGGGUAGAACAACAGAACUACAGAGUCUUACUUUUUGAUUUAACAUUUUAGUUUAGGUUCCAACUUCAUUCAGUGUUAUGUGAGAUGAUGGCCUCUUAUGAAAAACCUCAGUAAAAUUGACCAACAUUCCUUUAUUUUAAUUAUUAAAAAUUUUUUUUAAGAGAUAGGGUCUUGCUGCAUUGCCCAGACUAGUCUCCAAUUCCUGGGCUCAAGUAAUCCCCCCUCCUUAGCCUAAAAAAUUAUGUGUGCUUUUAAUCUAAAAUACCCAAAGGCUUUUUUUUUUUUUUUUUAAUCCAGUAAUUUUGUUGGAGUAUGUUUUAGGGUUGGUCGUUCUGAGUUCAUAGACUAAUUUUGAUUCAUGUUCUCUCUUGCCUUGUGUAAUUUUAAAAGUAUCUUUUAGCUACUAUAGAAAUAGUACAUUCUAGUUUUGAGCUGAGGAUGUCUUUCUUGCUUAUUCUCAUAGAGACAUCAUUCUGUUCUUUAUUCCCUCUAUUUUUUAUUUUUAUUUUUUUGAGACAGGAUCUCACUCUGUCACCCAGGCUGGAGUGCAGUGGCAUGAUUAUGACUCACUGUGGCCUCAACCUCCUGGGCUCCUCUCACCUCUGCCUCCCGAGUAGCUAGGACCACAGGCACGUGCACCCACUCCCAGCUAAUUUUUUUUUUUUUUUUUGAGAUGGAGUUUCACUCUUAUUCAGGCUGGGGUGCAAUGGUGUGAUCUCAGCUCGCUGCAACCUUCACCUCCAAGGUUUGAGCAAUUCUCCUGCCUCAGCCUCCCAAGUAGCUGGGAUCACAGGCAUGCACCACCACACCCAGAUAAUUUUGUAUUUUUAGUAGAAAUGGGGUUUUACCACGUUAGCCAGGCUGGUCUCGAACUCCUGACCUCAGAUGCUUCACCCUCUUUGGCCUCCCAAAGUGCUGGGAUUACAGGUGUGAGCCACGGCACCUGGCCUAAUUUUUGUAUUUUUUGUAGAGACAGGAUUUCUUUAUGUUACCCAGGCUGGUCUCGAACUCAUGGGCUCAAGCGAUCUGCCUCCCUCCACUACCGCCUCCCAAAGUGCUGGUAUUACAGGCUUUAGUCACAGGGACCUGGCCUCCCUUUUUUUUACUUUUAGUAACUUUGUAUGGGAUUUAACUUCUAUACUUUGUUUCCUUUUUAUGUGAAUUUAGUUUUCCUCAACUUUUAGAAGGAAGCUAGUCAAGAUAACGUUUCUAACUUCAUACAACUUCCUCUUCUGUUAAAAAAUUAUGGCACUUGUUUCCUAAGAAUUCCUGGCUCUGUCCCUGUGCCCCAUGUUAGUCUGUUCCUUCUCCCUUUUUCCUGUCCUGUUAGUUUUGGUCAUCUCCCAGCAGUGGCUCUUCAUAGCAGGCCCUCUCCUGGAAAGGAUCUCUGACUGGUUAGUGUCAAGGGUUCAUGGGGGUUAAACUCUCCUGGCCCCUUUAUGUCUUACCUUGGGUUCCCUGCCACUUGUGUACUAUUGGUGUGGGCAAACCUCCUCCUAGCGCGCUGCGGUUCUCUAAUUGGGUGCUGUGCCUUCUGGGUCGUACCUCUUGGGUGUUGGGAAUUCUCCUGUUUUCAGGUCCUUUAAUAAGGCUGGAUUGCUUCCCACGUAGGUGCUGUAGCACUAGGGUUUGUGGCUGUGGUAGUUUGUCACCACCAACUUGUAUUUUGGGGUUCUUGUAAAUGUCUUUGCUAUCUAGUUGUUCAGUAAUUAUGUGGGAUCCAAGAAAAUCACAAAACAUUUCCAUAAACAUUUCCAUCUCCACUUUUCCAGAAUCUGCUAGAUCUUCUUACCCUAUUCUUAAAGAGUUUGCUGUAUAUGGUUUAAUUUUUUCCUUAAUAUUUUUUCUUGAUAUCUUAAAAUAUAUCUAUGAAUAUUGCUUAUUUUAUUAUGAUGCACUCAGGGCAGUGAGGGAUAUUCACCUUAAGUCUUUAGGCAUUUGUCUUUUUAAUAGCUUUAUGUAAAUAGAUAUGGUAGAUUUUUCUAUCUUGUGAUGCUGAAUUUUAUUUGUCUCUGCAUUGAUGUGACUAAGUUUCUUUUUUCUCAUUAGGAUGGUUUUUCUAAUAUCUCGAAUCUAAUUAUCAAACUUUACAACUGUGUGUGAAGUGUGAGCAAAUAAAUGCCAGGUUUUGAGGGAGAGGAACUUUGCUUUUACUAGUGGGAGCCUUUUUGUUUUCUCCUGAAUUGUCAAAGCUGUGACAGUUGCUGCAUAGGCAAGGUCAUACCCACAGUAGAAGGAAAUAGGGCAAGGAUUCAGUUUCUUCAGUAAUCUCUUGUGUCACAGAAUUGAACAUUUAUUGCUAAGGAAACAGGAAAAUUCUUUUAAAAUACAUUUUUUGAGUAAAGAUUAGUUUACUUAAAUAAAUACAGGCAGUCCUUGCUAUGCAGGAUAAGUAAAACAGCUAAAAAUAAUAAUGCAAGCUGAAACCAUGCAAAGCAAUUUUAAUAGUCAGUGGGAAAAUUACAAUUGUUUUGUGAUCUUUAAAAAUUUUUGUUAAAUCACUAAAAACUUUUGUCAAUUACAAAAGUGUAGGGAAAUAAAAAAAUAGUAAAACUACUGUUUACUACAGUAUAAUUUAAAAUACUAGGAACAUUGAGAAUUAAAGUAUUUUAUUUCUUUGUAAAAAGCUUAUCAAUAGUAGUUUAAACAGCACUUCUCUGUGUCGUUUCUGUGCCUUGGUUGCUUCCAACAUUUUAUCCUUUGCAGUUUUAAUGUCAUGAAAUAUCUCCUAGAGUUGCUUUAAUGUGAAGUAUUUUCCUGGAGUCACUUCCUUUGGGACGUUGCCAUUCUUUCCAUCACAACCAGUUUCCUCACUGAUGUUGCUGGAGAAUGCUGGAGGAGACCUUAAGGAUGGCCACCACCACUAUGAAGGAGCUGUUGUCAUUCUGGAUGCUGGUGCUCAGUACGGGAAAGUCAUAGACCGAAGAGUGAGGGAACUGUUCGUGCAGUCUGAAAUUUUCCCCUUGGAAACACCAGCAUUUGCUAUAAAGGAACAAGGAUUCCGUGCUAUUAUCAUCUCUGGAGGACCUAAUUCUGUGUAUGCUGAAGAUGCUCCCUGGUUUGAUCCAGCAAUAUUCACUAUUGGCAAGCCUGUUCUUGGAAUUUGCUAUGGUAUGCAGAUGAUGAAUAAGGUAUUUGGAGGUACUGUGCACAAAAAAAGUGUCAGAGAAGAUGGAGUUUUCAACAUUAGUGUGGAUAAUACAUGUUCAUUAUUCAGGGGCCUUCAGAAGGAAGAAGUUGUUUUGCUUACACAUGGAGAUAGUGUAGACAAAGUAGCUGAUGGAUUCAAGGUUGUGGCACGUUCUGGAAACAUAGUAGCAGGCAUAGCAAAUGAAUCUAAAAAGUUAUAUGGAGCACAGUUCCACCCUGAAGUUGGCCUUACAGAAAAUGGAAAAGUAAUACUGAAGAAUUUCCUUUAUGAUAUAGCUGGAUGCAGUGGAACCUUCACCGUGCAGAACAGAGAACUUGAGUGUAUUCGAGAGAUCAAAGAGAGAGUAGGCACGUCAAAAGUUUUGGUUUUACUCAGUGGUGGAGUAGACUCAACAGUUUGUACAGCUUUGCUAAAUCGUGCUUUGAACCAAGAACAAGUCAUUGCUGUGCACAUUGAUAAUGGCUUUAUGAGAAAACGAGAAAGCCAGUCUGUUGAAGAGGCCCUCAAAAAGCUUGGAAUUCAGGUCAAAGUGAUAAAUGCUGCUCAUUCUUUCUACAAUGGAACAACAACCCUACCAAUAUCAGAUGAAGAUAGAACCCCACGGAAAAGAAUUAGCAAAACGUUAAAUAUGACCACAAGUCCUGAAGAGAAAAGAAAAAUCAUUGGGGAUACUUUUGUUAAGAUUGCCAAUGAAGUAAUUGGAGAAAUGAACUUGAAACCAGAGGAGGUUUUCCUUGCCCAAGGUACUUUACGGCCUGAUCUAAUUGAAAGUGCAUCCCUUGUUGCAAGUGGCAAAGCUGAACUCAUCAAAACCCAUCACAAUGACACAGAGCUCAUCAGAAAGUUGAGAGAGGAGGGAAAAGUAAUAGAACCUCUGAAAGAUUUUCAUAAAGAUGAAGUGAGAAUUUUGGGCAGAGAACUUGGACUUCCAGAAGAGUUAGUUUCCAGGCAUCCAUUUCCAGGUCCUGGCCUGGCAAUCAGAGUAAUAUGUGCUGAAGAACCUUAUAUUUGUAAGGACUUUCCUGAAACCAACAAUAUUUUGAAAAUAGUAGCUGAUUUUUCUGCAAGUGUUAAAAAGCCACAUACCCUAUUACAGAGAGUCAAAGCCUGCACAACAGAAGAGGAUCAGGAGAAGCUGAUGCAAAUUACCAGUCUGCAUUCACUGAAUGCCUUCUUGCUGCCAAUUAAAACUGUAGGUGUGCAGGGUGACUGUCGUUCCUACAGUUACGUGUGUGGAAUCUCCAGUAAAGAUGAACCUGACUGGGAAUCACUUAUUUUUCUGGCUAGGCUUAUACCUCGCAUGUGUCACAACGUUAACAGAGUUGUUUAUAUAUUUGGCCCACCAGUUAAAGAACCUCCUACAGAUGUUACUCCCACUUUCUUGACAACAGGGGUGCUCAGUACUUUACGCCAAGCUGAUUUUGAGGCCCAUAACAUUCUCAGGGAGUCUGGGUAUGCUGGGAAAAUCAGCCAGAUGCCGGUGAUUUUGACACCAUUACAUUUUGAUCGGGACCCACUUCAAAAGCAGCCUUCAUGCCAGAGAUCUGUGGUUAUUCGAACCUUUAUUACUAGUGACUUCAUGACUGGUAUACCUGCAACACCUGGCAAUGAGAUCCCUGUAGAGGUGGUAUUAAAGAUGGUCACUGAGAUUAAGAAGAUUCCUGGUAUUUCUCGAAUUAUGUAUGACUUAACAUCAAAGCCCCCAGGAACUACUGAGUGGGAGUAAUAAACUUCUUGUUCUAUUAAAGUACCGUGUGCAGUUUAAAUUGAUUAGAAAUCAUUCCCAUUAUUGACAUGCAGUACUGUGAAAAGAGUUACUGGAGCAGCUACAUCACAUCUGAGUUCUCCACAGCAAAAAUCUACGGCUUAAGAGCUGAGUUGGGGAUAACCAAAAGGGACUGAAGAGUUUGUACGGGUAAAUAAUCAAAGCACCAUUGCCUACACUCAGACAGAUUGAUACUGCUUUUGCCUUUGCCUCACUUAUUCUUUAUGUAUAAAUUCACUGUUGAUGUCUCUGUGAAUAUGUAUGAAGGUGGGUGAAUUUGGGGGUAAUUAUGGGCUUCUGUCUCCUUACCAGUUUCUAAGAACUGUUAGAAACGCCCAUUAUUUACCAGUGUUACUUACUACUUAUAUAUACUUUUUGGAGAAUCAGUUUUCUUAUAAGUAAUCUUAUUUCUCCAAAGGGUGAAAAAGAGAUGAACAUAUCAGAUAAAGGUAUAGGUGGGCUAUUCCAGCCACUUUUGAAGGACACUGAGGGUAUAAAAUGUAAGCUACCAUAAGAUGGAAAAGCACCAGGAAUUUGUUGAUGUACUUUUGAAUUUUAUUUCACAGCCUUGGGAGGAAGAAACUAUGAGUGGUCUCAGAUGUCUAUGAAUGGUCUUAAAAUGUUUUCAAACCAUGUUCCACAUAGAUGCCAUGUUAUUCAAUGUCAGCUUGUUUAUUAGUAAGGAGCUUUAUCCUCCUAGCCUUAUAUUACCAGCCCCCCACAGCCUUGCAUAGAAAGUUUCUGUUAUCUCCUUAGAAGAAACUGGCUCAAUGACGUUUCUGGUGUAGUGCAGAUAGAGGUCAAGAGGAGCAUUUUCAUCUCUUCUUUUGCUGGUCAGAGAAACGGUUCUGAGAUCACAGAAGCUAUGAUGCAUACCUACAGCUUACAAAAGGGAGAGGAAAAAUGUUUAUAUCAUCUAGUAAACAGUUGUAAAAUGAGCUUUUAAAUCUAAUCUAUAGACAUAUUAUUCAUUGCUCAGACACCUGUGAACAGUCUUGAUACAUGCAAGAUGUUUGCCAAACUUUGUAAUCCUUUCUACUAGCUAUAAGAGAGGAUUUAAGAACUGGUGUAGGACUUGUUGCCAUCACCACCAGUUUCUAACAGAUCUUUUAUAACAUUCACAUAAGUACUGUAGACAGUAGUAGACUUAAACUCUCCGUUUCUCUCAGUAUUUUAGCUAAGAAUGUUACCAUAUUUUUCUCUUAACAAUUCCAUCUCAGGUUGCUGCUGCUUGUCUAGUUUAAAAGGUCAGAUCUAUUAAUCAGGAAUGAAAUUUUAUUUGGGAUUCAGUGUUAGACAAACAACAAAAUGAUGCGUGGCAGAAGUCAUCUUUUUAUUCUGGCUGGUCCAGGGAACAAGAAAACUGCUGCUGGACCAGCAAGGGAAGAGUUUCUGUCUGUCUUAACAGAAAUCUGUCCCCAAGACAAAGGGGUACUUGACUCCUACAAAACUUAAAGGGUACAUUCUCUAUCUGAUGAGGAGGUACUCAUUAUGGCCUUCUGGAAAGAGGCUAUGUUAGUGAUCUGGUCUUUACAGAUUUAGAGUCAUGUUAUUUGAAAGCUAGAAUAGACAACCUAUAAAAUGCUUACCAACAUGUGUCAGUACACGUUUAUGUUUAUAUGAAAAAAAAUUUCUAGCCACAGUGUCUUAUGAUUUUGUAUUGAAGCAAACAGUAGGAAUUUUGGAAAAAUAGAGAGUAAGAAUGUGUGUUCUAUGGAACACUGCUCCACUGAGAAGGUCCAUGUAAAAAGGAUUAGGUGGUCAUAUAAGUUUGGGGAACAUAAGCUCACUUGUCCUUUCCUGGAGAUUCAUGGUAUAUAAUAUUCAAAGCUCUGAGAAAUUCUGAAGUUAAAAACAAUUGUUAAAUUCUGCUUAAAUUAGUGUUUUCCUGAUAUUUGUUUUUUGAACACCUUUUAUAUAAUCCCUUCUAAUAUAUACUUAGUAUAUACUUAAUAUAAUAUUGGGAAAAUUGUUACUCCAAAGCACAUCUUGACAUGACAUAGUUUCUUAAAAAUCCAAAUUUUCUGGAACUCAGAAAUUUCCUAAUAUUUAGCACACUGUCUUCUUUUGCACAGCACUUUUUGCUUUGUGCCAUAUAGCAUUACUCUGUACCUUCACAGUAUUUCAUCUGAGCCACUGAGGAAAGUUAAAGGUUGCACUUCCAUUUUACAGUUAAGAAAACAAGCUCACCUUAGGCAUGGUUACUUAAUUAAUUUCAGAAUUAAAUUUCAGGUUUCCUUAGUCCAGAUUGUCCUGAUGUGUAUUCUGACACCUAAAAUUAUAUAAACAUUUAUGGGAUGCUUAUUUUACUAAGACUAGAAUGGUGGCUACCUGGCUAAUAACAUUCAUCAUUGGUUAUUCUGGGCAUAUCAUGACUUUAUUCCCGUUGCUUACCAUCUACCUGGGACACAUCUCUCUUUGAUUAAAUAUAUUCUUUUUCUUUGUACUUUUUAGGUAGACAGAGAAUGUAGAUCAUUGAAAGCAUUAUUUAUUCCUAAGAUUGGCAGGCACAGAAUCAUUUUUAAGAACCAAAUACCCAGUCCUGCCUUAAAGGCCACAUCUAUGAUCAUCAGCUCUGUUAGAAAUAACAGCCUGGCAUAAUUCCUAAAUACAAGUCUGUAGAUAUAUCCAGGAGAUAGGGUUACACUGUUUUCUAACCUUUUUUAAAUCCCUUAAUCUUGAGGUAAACUGCAUGCAUUUAGUCAAACAAGCAUCAUAAAAUUUGUUUCCUCACUGUUUGGGCUUAACCUCCUGAUAGCCUGUUUUACUGAAUAACUUGACCCUAACCUGUAGAGAAUAAGAGCAUUCAAAUUAGGAAGGCAGGACUAUCCAUCUUUAGUGCUUUUCCUGCCGUUAAACAACAAUGUGAACUUGGUCAAGUCAUUUCUGUUCUUUAUCUGUGACAUGAGGUAACUGUAUUAAAUUUUCAGCAUCAAAUCCAGCUAUAAAUUUGUAUUUUGUAAACAAGAGAAAGUAAAGCAGGAGACAGAAUGGAGAAGCUGGAUAGUGUUUUUUUUUUUUUUUUUUAAGGUUCUUUUAUCAUCAGAUAUGACACAAAGGGAAACAUCAAAAUGCACCGUAAAGUUAAAUCCUAGUUACCUUUUUUUGAAGCUGUUGGCAAGGUUUGACCACUUGGGGCAUCUUCUGCUGUGAGAUGACACUUGAAAAACACCCAUCAAAGUUUUCCUGGUAGGAAUCUCUCUUUACUGCGUGUUUUUUUGAAAAGCUGACAGAGAAUAUGCUUUGGCUUUGACACUAAUGAAGUCACCCAUCAUCAAUUACAUACAGCUAAUUGUUGGGAGCUAGAGCUAGAAUCCAAGCUUUCUGAUUCUCUGCAUGGAAGAGGAAAUGCUCUAGGGCCCUUCAGGGCAAAUCUUAAAAGGAAGUUCUUGGCCGGGCGCGGUGGCUCAUGCCUGUAAUCCCAGCACUUUGGGAGGCCGAGGUGGGUGGAUCACGAGAUCAGGAGAUCGAGACCAUCUUGGCUAACACGGUGAAACCCCAUCUCUACUAAAAAUACAACAAAUUAGCUGGGCGCGGUGGCGGGUGCCUGUAGUCCCAGCUACUCGGGAGGCUGAGGCAGGAGAAUGGCCUGAACCCAGGAGGCGGAGCUUGCAGUGAGCUGAGAUAGUGCCACUGCACUCCGGCCUGGUGAAAGAGCGAGACUCAGUCUCAAAAAAAAAAAAAAAAGGAAGUUCUUAGUGUGUAAUUGACCAUCAGGGAUAAAUGGGCUUCAAAAGUGUUAAUUGUCUCCUUACUUACAGUGAGUUUCUAGAGAUAGCCCUGUCUUUCAGAAAUUCUCUGACAUCUGCUUGCGCAAUGUUAUAACCACUUUCCCACACUACUCCCCUCCAGAAAUCUCAUUGAUAUGUGGCGAGGACACGCCUUAGCUAUCACCCCAAUGGAUGCUUCUUUCAUUGACCCAAAUCCAGAAUGUAAUGGGGAACUGAAUACAAGUUGGAUGUCUCCACCCUUGGAAAGCACAUCUUUUGUUCUUACUGAAGUAGUUUAACACCACCAGAUGAUCAAGGGAUCAGGGUAUCUUUCUGGUAUCUUUUUAAUCACUGAAGGACUUUGACAGCAGUAAUGGUGGCAUUGUUGACUCUUAAAUUUCUGAACGUUUCACUUAAUGGCAAGUGAAGAGAUAUAGAAUCCCCCAAAGAGUGUCAAGAUGCUAACUUCCAACCCUAUUUUUAUGUACUGAAGAGGCCUCAGUGUCUCACUGAACUCUAACCUUUUUGUCAGUGUUCCUCAACACUGGAUGCGUAUUAUUACAUAACCUGAGGAGUUAAAAAAUACAAUAACCAGAUGUCCAAUUAAAUAAAAUUAGAAUCUGGAGGAGGUAGAACUCAAGCAUUUACAGUUUUGUUUUGUUUUUUUUUUAAGACAGAGUCUCGCUCUGUCCCCAAGUGCAGUGGCACAAUCUCGGCUCACUGCAAGCUCCGCUUCGUGGGUUCACGCCAUUCUCCUGCCUCAGUCUCCCGAGUAGCUGGGACUACAGGCGCCCGCCACUACGCCCGGCUAAUUUUUUUGUACUUUUUAGUAGAGACAGGGUUUCACUGUGUUAUACAGGAUGGUCUCGAUCUCCCGACCUCAUGAUCCGCCCGCCUCGGCCUCUCAGAGUGCUGGGAUUACAGGCGUGAGCCACCACGCCCGGCAAGCAUUUACAGUUUUAAAUCUCCCAGUCAGAAUAAAUUCUUAUUGAGGGCCAUACCUAGCCUGUCUUCAUCAAACUCAUAGGUGAAUCUUUGUCAAACCUAUAGGAGAGAGAUGCAGGCCAUAGAGAUGGUCUUGCUGAAGGUCUUAUAGCUAAAUUAGUUCAGAUCCAGGAACCAGAUUCUGGAACUGAUUGCACCUAUAUUAUGUUGUGUGUCAGACACUCCCAGGACCUGUUUGGUAAUAAUUAGGACAGCUGACAUACUUGUUGCUAAUUUUGAGAUCUGGGCAACAACUGUGUAGGCUGUUCUUUCAACCUCUUUCUUCUUACUUCUUUACUUUUCCUUCAGAGAGGAGAAAGCCACCCCUGUGCUAUAGCCACCGCUCCAAUUCUGACUCUAGCUAGGUCAUGAAACAGACUGAGCUAUUAUUGCAUCAACACAUAAAUCCUGUCAUUUGGGUAUUAUUCUUUAGAGAACUAGAGAUUACCUAGCUGCAACCUAAGUUUCCUGAAUUAGAAUCAUUUGAGCAGCACCAUCUUAAUUGGCUCAUUAACAUAUUUGUGACCAGGCACAGUGGCGCAUGCCUGUAAUCCCAGCACUUUGGGAGGCCGAGGCGGGCGGAUCUCUUGAGGUCAGGAGUUUGAGACCAGCGUGGCCAACAUGGUGAAACCCCAUUUCUACUAAAAAUGUAAAAAUUAGCUGGGCUUGGUGGCGCGCGCCUGUAAUCCCAGCUACUCGGAAGGCUGAGGUGUGAGAAUCACUUAAACCCGGGAGAUGGAGGUUGCAGUGAGCAGAGAUUGCGCCACUGCACUCCAGCCUAGGUGACAAGAAUGAGACUCCGUCUUAAAACAAAAACAACAUAUUUGUUCACUUUUGAACCCUGUGGUGUCUUUUAACUUUGUUAAGGGCCCUUGGUUAGCAAAAUUAUGAAAGUUUAGGAAAUUUGGCUAUUGAGUAUAUUAAGUACAACUACAAAAUCCUCUGAGUUCUCCAGGAAGCCUAAACCUUGAGCAGUAUCUUAUUCAAGUGGAGUAUAUAUCUUCAAGAAUACAGAUUUUUAAGGUAAGUAGUUUUUCGUCUUUGCAUCUCCUAAGACCAUUGUUAACAACCUUGAUAUUAAACGAAGAAGUGAAUGUAAACCUCCUUUUGAACAUAUUUUUUAUAAAGAAAUAUUUUGUUAAUUGGAGUAAGUAGUAUUGUUAUGAAAUCACUGUGUAAUUGUUAAUUGUAAACUGCAAUGUCUAUUUUGUGUUGUAACAAUGUUGCCAUAAAAUAGCUUUGCUAAAUGUGAAAUGACUUUAAUCCCUUUUGUCUUCAAUAUACUUCAUAAAGGAGGAAAUGAUGAUUUACACAAUUUGUCAUGAAGCUUCCGUGUUUAUGAGAAAUUCCAAGAAGUAAGAGCCAAGAGGACAGAUAUUAUCAGAAUAUGGGACAUAAGAAAUUGCAUAUAGUGUCAAGGGUUUCUAUAUAACAACUUAAUUUAUUUCCCUUGCAUAUAUAGUAGGGGUUAACAUUUUGCUCAAUGUUAACGGGGGACAUAAUGGACAUAAAACAUUGGAUAGCUUUUUAUUUAAAUGAGCUAAAGGUGUGCGUAUACACAUGCACUUAUAAAAUUAAAGUCAUAUAUGUAUAUA